CAAACUUGGUUCCAGCUGCGUGUGGUGAAAGCAACUAGAGGCAGAGCUAUCAAGGGCUGUGACAGAUGAGCAGUGGUCUGUCUGCAAUGAGCAUGUGCUCAAGCUAACAUGGAUACCAUCUUGGUCUUCAGCCUAAUCAUUGCAUCCUAUGAUGCCAACAAGAAAGACCUCAGAGAUAGCAGUUGCCGACUGGAACAGCUGCCUGGGAUCUUCCCAAAAGACGUGAGAAGCAUCAGAGAAUUGCAAAUGCAAGAAACUCACACAGAAACCAAAAGGACAACAUUCAUUCAAAACCGGACUAUAGCUACCCUGCAGUGCCUUGGCUCUGACAGCAAAGUAAAAGUCAACCUUGUAUAUUUGGAGAGAAGGCCAAAGGUCAAGCAUAUUUUGAAGAACCUGAGAAUCAUUGCUGCUCCCCGCAGAAACAGCUCUGCCUCCUCAAGCUGUCACCUAAUCCCCACAUCCAAGUUUCAGACUGGAUCUCUUCUAAAAGGCAAAGCUUUUUUACCAGGGAUCUCACAAUGUAAAGUCCUGGGGGCUUCAUCAGAGACUUUUCCCACCACUGCCCCUUCUAUAACUCCUGGGAAUAAAGAAGGAGAGAAAACUACAAGUACCGACACAGAUGAGAACCUAGAGAAGAGACAGAAAUGGAGUAUUGUGGUCAAAAUUCUGAUUGCUGUCACCCUGUUGCUCAGUGGAGUUGCCAUUAUAGUAUUUGUAAUUUUUGAAGUCCCAUGUCCUUAUCAAUGCCUAGGAGCCAGGAAGCUGUGCCAAUGCCAGUGGUUGUGGAGAUGGCAAAAGAAGGGAGGCCAGCCACCUGGGACAGCUGAAUCCAAGCCUGACUCUCAGCCCCAGAAGGUUGGACAAGAUGCUGCCAAUUCAUCAAACCCAAAGAAAGCUGCAGAGAUCACUGUUAUCCACCAGACAUACUUCUGAAAAGUUCUGCUCUAUCUCAAAGACUGAAUGAUACUACACAGUCCUCUCCCUAUUAAUAUGGGCACAUUCUUGCCAAUUUCACACUUGUAUCUUCAGCAGGGACAUUACAAUCAAACACCAAUUCCUGGUUAAUGAAGGGAGAGUGUGGGCUUAGCAGAGUUACCCUCAUGCCCCUAUCUGAGCCACAACCUUCUGUAAUUCACUUCAUACAUCCAUCUAAAUGGAUACCUUUCCAUCCCCUCAAACGAGAACAAAAAGUAUUCCCUGCAAGCACUAUGAAUGGACCUUACUACUCUCUUUGACAGAAGACUCAAACACAGCCUCUAAGAAACAAGGCAGCUGUUAGUGUGACAUAGCUUCCAGCUCCUCUGUUAUCUUCACAGCUGACUUCACACUCACUGGCCCUCAAUAGCUUAGAGUGGGACUCCUGAUCUCCCUGGUUGACGUUUAUAAGGUUUUGUAAUUUAGCUUCUGGUACUACAUGUAUCUAUCCACACACUGCUGAAGGGAACUUGACCCUACGCAUUCCAAAAGCCUUCCUCAUAAGUUAUCCCCAAGGGGUUCAGGGACUACAGACCAUUAGUACCCAAGUGAAGUCUUCUGACGAUCCAGAAUUCCUAAGGUGGCUCUGAUAUUAUAUCAUACUUUAAUAGAGAGUUGCAUACCUUUUGGACAAAGAUUCCAGAGCAAAAUAAUUAUGAUAAUGCUGUUUCUCACAGGAGAAUAGCUAUGAGUCAAAUCUAACCUGCUUAAAUAAGAGUUUGGUGAGAAAGUGAAACCACCUGAUCUUGAAUCAAUGUUGAGGUGAAAAAGGAAAUGUCAGGAGGGAUAAGACAGGGUGAGGCCCUGCUUCUUUUCCUAAGAGUCUGAAACCAUUCCAUUUCAUUUUGGUGAAAUGUGUCUGUUUCUAAGAAAUUCUGUUUUCUUAGUUCUCUGGUUAAAAAAAAAAAUACAUAAACUGUAUCCUUCUUUCUUUCACUUCAA